GACAGAGCGGCUGACGGAGCCGGGCUCACCAGGUCGCUGCCGCGAGGGAGUUGCUGUGCUGGGGCCUGGGUGGCGGCUGGAGGCCUGAGUUGGGCUCGCGGCGGGGGUCGGCAGGGGGCCGGGUGGCGGAAUGAUGGAGGAGGAGGAACUGGAGUUCGUGGAGGAGCUGGAAGCCGUGCUGCAGCUCACGCCCGAGGUGCAGCUGGCCAUCGAGCAGGUGUUUCCAAGCCAGGACCCUCUAGAUCGAGCAGAUUUCAAUGCUGUUGAGUAUAUCAAUACCCUGUUCCCAACCGAGCAAUCUCUGGCGAACAUAGACGAAGUCGUGAACAAAAUUAGGCUGAAAAUAAGGAGACUGGAUGACAAUAUUCGAACUGUUGUAAGAGGUCAGACGAACGUGGGGCAGGAUGGACGGCAAGCGCUUGAAGAGGCUCAGAAAGCUAUCCAACAACUCUUUGGCAAAAUCAAAGAUAUCAAAGACAAAGCUGAAAAAUCAGAGCAAAUGGUGAAAGAAAUCACCCGUGAUAUUAAGCAAUUAGAUCACGCCAAACGCCACCUGACCACCUCAAUCACCACACUGAACCACCUGCACAUGCUGGCAGGAGGUGUCGACUCCCUCGAAGCCAUGACCAGGCGAAGACAAUACGGAGAAGUUGCUAAUCUCCUUCAGGGUGUGAUGAAUGUCCUGGAGCACUUCCACAAGUAUAUGGGGAUUCCGCAGAUCCGGCAGCUUUCCGAAAGAGUGAAGGCUGCACAGACUGAGUUAGGACAGCAAAUCCUGGCAGAUUUUGAAGAAGCGUUUCCUUCCCAGGGCACCAAGAGACCAGGAGGACCCAGCAAUGUUCUACGAGAUGCAUGUCUGGUUGCUAAUAUUCUAGAUCCCAGGAUCAAACAGGAAAUCAUCAAAAAGUUUAUUAAACAGCAUCUGUCAGAGUAUCUGGUACUUUUUCAAGAAAACCAAGAUGUUGCCUGGCUGGACAAAAUCGACAGACGCUAUGCCUGGAUAAAACGCCAGCUUGUGGACUAUGAGGAGAAAUACGGCCGCAUGUUUCCACGUGAGUGGUGCAUGGCUGAGAGGAUUGCGGUGGAAUUUUGCCAUGUGACAAGGGCAGAACUUGCCAAGAUUAUGCGUACCAGAGCGAAGGAAAUUGAAGUGAAAUUGCUUCUUUUUGCUAUUCAAAGAACAACUAACUUUGAGGGGUUUCUUGCAAAACGCUUCUCCGGCUGCACCCUGACCGAUGGGACCCUGAAAAAGCUUGAGUCUCCACCCCCAUCUACCAAUCCCUUCCUGGAAGAUGAGCCAACACCAGAGAUGGAGGAACUGGCAACGGAGAAAGGAGAUUUAGAUCAACCAAAGAAGCCUAAAGCCCCAGACAAUCCAUUUCAUGGCAUUGUUUCCAAGUGUUUUGAGCCUCAUCUCUACGUGUAUAUCGAAUCCCAAGACAAGAACCUCGGAGAGCUGAUAGAUCGGUUUGUGGCUGAUUUCAAAGCCCAGGGGCCACCUAAGCCCAACACUGAUGAAGGGGGUGCCGUGCUCCCCAGCUGCGCCGACCUCUUUGUCUACUACAAGAAGUGCAUGGUGCAAUGCUCUCAGCUCAGUACUGGGGAGCCCAUGAUCGCCCUGACCACCAUUUUCCAGAAGUACCUCCGAGAAUACGCCUGGAAAAUCCUCUCUGGCAACCUGCCCAAAACCACAACCAGCAGUGGAGGACUGACUAUCAGCAGCCUCCUCAAGGAAAAGGAGGGCUCAGAAGUAGCCAAGUUCACUCUGGAGGAGCUCUGCCUCAUCUGUAACAUCCUGAGCACGGCAGAGUACUGUCUGGCCACCACCCAGCAGCUAGAAGAAAAACUCAAAGAAAAAGUGGAUGUAAGUCUGAUUGAACGAAUCAAUCUGACUGGAGAGAUGGACACGUUCAGCACCGUCAUCUCCAGCAGUAUUCAGCUGCUGGUUCAGGAUCUGGAUGCUGCCUGUGAUCCUGCCCUGACUGCCAUGAGCAAGAUGCAGUGGCAGAACGUGGAGCACGUUGGUGACCAGAGCCCCUACGUCACCUCUGUCAUUCUGCACAUCAAGCAGAACGUCCCCAUCAUCCGUGACAACCUGGCUUCCACACGCAAGUACUUCACUCAGUUCUGCGUUAAAUUUGCAAACUCCUUCAUUCCCAAAUUCAUCACCCACCUCUUCAAGUGCAAGCCAAUUAGCAUGGUGGGAGCAGAACAGCUGCUGCUGGACACCCACUCGCUGAAGAUGGUCCUGCUCGAUCUCCCCUCCAUCAGCUCGCAGGUGGUGAGGAAGGCACCCGCCAGCUACACCAAGAUCGUUGUCAAAGGCAUGACCCGGGCUGAGAUGAUCCUCAAGGUAGUGAUGGCCCCUCAUGAACCGUUGGUGGUGUUUGUUGACAACUACAUCAAACUUCUCACAGACUGCAACACAGAAACCUUUCAGAAGAUACUGGACAUGAAGGGGCUGAAGAGGAGUGAGCAGAGCAGCAUGCUGGAACUCCUGCGCCAGCGGCUCCCCGCACCGCCCUCGGGGGCAGAAAGCUCCGGCUCACUGUCCCUGACGGCGCCAACACCAGAGCAAGAGUCGUCACGCAUCCGCAAGCUCGAGAAACUCAUUAAAAAGAGACUGUAGCAGCAGCAAGGGGCCCUUUGCUCCUGGCUGGAGACCCUCAGCGCCCGUUCCCCAGAAGCCCCCAACCUCUCCUGUGCUCCCCGGCACUCUCACAUCGUCGGUCUUCAAACUUCCUGGGACAUGUGGGUUGUUACUGAGUCUCUCCCAUGCCCUGUCUUACUUCCUGCCCUAAUCGGAGACGCUGAGUAAGGGCUGGGCUCUAAGAGGGCGAUUUAGGUGAUCUCUGGUUCGUGAAGCAGAGGCAGCAGUGGAGGAUAGGUCCCUGAGCUGCCCUUGACUCAUGUAGCCUCCCCAUGGCAGUCACACCCUCUUGACACGUGGGCCCCACCCGUCCUUUUUUUUUUUUUUUUUUUUUUUUUUUGAGACAGAGUCUCGCUCUGUCACCCAGGCUGGAGUGCAGUGGCGUGAUCUCGGCUCACUGCAACCUCCGCCUCCCAGGUUCAAGCAAUUCUCCUGCCUCAGCCUCCUGAGUAUCGGAUUACAGGCGUGAGCCACCGAGCCCAGCCCCUUCCUCCAUUUCUUUACUCCCACCCUGCUCCUGGUUUCUAGGGAAGGGAAACCAGGAAGUUCACUUGGAAGACGUUUCCUAGGUUUUCUCAUCAGAUGAAGCCAUGGGAACGCCCAGGAAGUCCAUACUCUCAAACCCCUUUCUGCCCACUCACCUUCAGGUCCACAGCACUUUCCAGCGUCAUCUGAAAUAGCAAAGGUGAUGUGCAGCAUCCCAGUGAUGUGUUCCUGUGUUAUGAGAAGGAGUCUGGGGUUCUGGAUGCCUCAGGAACAGAAUAUGGACCUUAAAGACCAGGCUGAGAGCCUGGCCUGGCACGCAGCCUGCCCGCCCCCCCCGCCCUUCCUGUCCACCGCGGGCUCUCUGCAGCAGGGCUUGCCGAAGAGACUGCUCCCGACCUCUCAUGUCAUCCUGCAUCCAGAGAAUGGCAGCAUAUCAAGCCGUUAACCCUGAUUCACUCGGUUCCCUUGAAACCAGGCCUCAGUUAACCAUGACCACAGCUACAGGCAAACCGCUGCUGUUGCUGCCUGCUUUUGCUGAAGAAUGAUAUCUUGCCAGGCACGGCGGCUCAUGCCUGUAGUCGCAACACUUUGGGAGACCAAGGCAGGAGGAUCACUUGAGUCCAGGAGUUUGAGACCAGCCUGGGCAACAUACAGAUGUCUACAAAAAUAAAAAUUUGCAAGGUGUGGUGGCAUGCACCUGUAGUCCCAACUGCUAGGGAGGCUGAGGUGGGCAGAUUGCUUGAGCUCAGGAGUUUGAGACCAGUCUGGGCAACCUGGCAAAACCAAAAAUACAAAAAAUUGGCUGGGUGUGGUGGCUCAUGCCUGUAAUCACAGCACUUUGGGAGGCUGAGGCAGGUGGAUCACCUGAGGUCAGGAAUUCGAGACCAGCCUGCCCAACAUGGCGAAACCCUGUCUCAACUAAAAAUAAAAAAAAUUAGCCGGGUGUCAUGGCGAGUGCCUGUAAUCCCAGCUACUGGGGAGGCUGAGGCAGGAGAAUCACUUAAACCCGGGAGGUGGAGGCUGCAGUGAGCCAAGAUUUCACCACUGCACUCCAGCCUGGGUGACAGAGCAAGACCCCUUCUCAAAAAGUUUUCAGGAUAGAGGAAAUUUCCUUAAAAUCCAUAAAACUUGUAACAGCCGUACAGUAGGAAUAAGGUUUGGAAAUCUGCCUGGAAACCUGAUUUCCUCAUCCCCACCUUGUUUCCCAACAUAACCACUGCUCUGUGCCCCUGCCCUCUCUGCCAGGCUUUCUCCCCGAUGCCGUCCAGCUCUGAUCCUGAGUGUCAUUUCUUCAUCGGCUUCCAGGCUGUCCUUGCUAGCUGGUUUGACUCUCACGCAUCAAGCGUCUCAAAUUUGAGAAUGCGGAGGAGAAAAGAAGUGUUGCGAGAAGGAGAUGCGGCCUUCAGUUGAGGUCUAUUAGGAAAAGAUUCCAAAUAAGACAAGGGCGGGGGGCGGCAGUCGGGAGAGCCCCCAGGAAGCCCUGUAGAUGCCCCCACCCCAGCCCAUGGAGUUGCUAUGGUUAAGCAGCCUGAGCCGUACAGUUGAAAAGGGGCGGUGGGGCCCAUCUCCAAAUAGCACAGCCAGUUCAGCCGUCUGUCCUCAACCCAGGAGAGCUGGGAAAGCCAGUGGACUCCUGCACCUGGUUCUUGUCACUCCUGGCGUUUGUGUACAGAUCACCACUUCUCUUUUUGGUUCAUUGUUGAGGAGUCGUUUUCCGGACGGCUCCAUCACAGCAUUGAGCUAUCAAGCUGCUGUUUUCCACAGUUGGUGGUCACAGCCAGGGAAGUUGCUGUCUUGAUUUGUUACAUUGUCAGUAAUCCCCAAGGAACCAAUGGAUGUCAGUAGGAGUUUCUGUUAAAUGUCUCCUUGAUGGGGACUCAGUACUGUGUAGAGACGCUGUGUUUCUCUUCUGGGGGUGUGCAUCAGAACCACUGGGGCCUUUUAAAAUCUACAGAUGCCGGCCGGGCGCCGUGGCUCACGCCUGGAAUCCCAGCACUUGGGGAGGCUGAGGCGGGCGGAUCACAAGCGCAGGAAAUUGAGACCAUCCUUGCCAAUAUGGUGAAACCCCAUCUCUACAAAAAAUACAAAAAUUACCGGGGUGUGGUGGCGUGCACACCUCCCAGCUACUUGGGAGGCUGAGGCAGGAGAAUCGCUUGAACCCGGGAGGCAAAGAUUGCAGUGAGCCGAGAUCACGCCACUGCACUCCAGCCUGGCGACAGAGUGAGACUCUAUCUCAAAACAAACAAAAAAACAGAUGCCCGGAGAUUUUGAGUCAGUAAGUUUGGAUGGGGCCUGGCAUACAGGUUUAAAAGUUCCAUAGGUAGUUAUAACGUUUACACCUUGUUAAGAACCACUGCAACAGAGAGAUUUGCUUUAUGGAAGGGCUCCUGCCACGCAUUUUCAUACAUGUCUAUUUUUCUGACUCUAAGCUAAAAGUGCGCCGACACUACACUUGAGCUGGUGCCAACGUGGUGAAGAUUCUCUACUGAUAACAGCUUUCAUUUUAAACUUGUGUUGGGUCAGGCGCGGUGGCUCACGCCUGUAAUCCCAGCACUUUGGGAGGCCGAGGUGGGCGGAUCACAUGAGGUCACGAGUUUGAGACCAGCCUGGCCAACAUGGCAAAAUCCCAUCUCUACUAAAAAUACAAAAAAAAAAAAAAAAAAAGCAGGCAGGUGGCGGGUGCCUGUAAUCCCAGCUACUUGGGAGGCUGAGGCAGGGGAAUCAGUUGAAUCCGGGAGGCGGAGGUUGCAGUGAGCCGAGGUCCCGCCACUGCACUCCAGCCUGGGAGACAGAGUGAGACUCAGUUAAAAAAAAAAGACUUUUGGUGGUGGUGGGGACCAUGCCCAGGAUUGGGCUCUCUCCAUACUGAUGAGGAUUCUUCUUGUUUUGAUGACCAACCCCCAAGCAGAAGCUUUAUUUAUUAACAUCACUUCAAAAAUAACGUAUCAAAGGGGCACCCUAGGCCGGGUACUGUGGCAUCACACCUGUAAUGCCAGUGCUUUGAGAGGCUGAGGUGGGAAGAUUGCUUGAGCCCAGGACUUCAAGACAAGCCUGGGCAACAGAGUGAGACCCCAUCUCUAUUAAAAAAUAGGCCGGGCAUGGUGGCUCACACUGGUAAUCCCAGCACUUUGGGAGGCCGAGGCAGGUGGAUCAUGUGAGGUCAGGAGUUCGAGACCAGCCUGGCCGACAUGGUGAAACCCUGUCUUUACUAAAAAUACAAAAUUAGCCAGGCGUGGUGGUGGGCGCCUGUAAUCCCAGCUACUCAGGAGGCUGAAGCAGGAGGAUCGCUUGAACCCAGGAGGCAGAGGCUGCAGUGAGCCGAGAUCAUGCCAUUGCACUCCUGCCUGGGUGACGGAGCAAGACUCUCUAAAAAAUAAUAAGGUAAAAGGAGUACCUGUGGAUGAAAGCAGCAGCUAACAGCUCUGUGAUUCAGCUAGACCUAGAUAUUGUGCCCAUUCCUUCCCCUCAGUCCAUUUUCUGUAGCCCCUUUAAAAACCAAAAAACAACUUUGAAGUCACUUUGGGUUUAAAAUAAAUAGUGGUAAUUUGUAUAAUCAAUAAAGAGUUCACUCUGCUCUUACUGAGGGGACUUGUCUGAAAGCUGGCUUAGCGGUGUCCAGGCCAGAGAACAUCCUGUGUGGACUCUUAACAAUGAAACAGGAGCCGCAAUGGACAAGGUGUUCUGAUCUCCAAACCCAGCUCAGGGAUUGAAGCUAACUACCGCCACUCCUUCCUCUCUCGAAGAACAAAGAGCCAGUACCCAGGGCUCUGCCCACCCCCGAGAAGGGGUGCCUGAUUUCUUAUGUCUAGGGUGGCUCCUCUGUGCAGAUCAGACAGGACUGAGAGCAGACAAGCUGAGACCAGCAUGACCAGUACAGGGCACGCAGAGCGUGGGGGCAGGUCCGAGGCUGCUGCUCGAUGCAGGGUAUGACACCAACCCUUCCUGAAUUGCCAUCGGAUGAGGAGACCUGGUUCCCUGUUGAAAGAAUGCCAGGGGAAAUGCUGCAUGUGCACAGCUGGAAAUGGGGUUCCUUCUCUAGGAAGAGCACUCGGAAUAACCUGCUGGAAAUGGGGUUCCUUCCCUAGGAAGAGCACUCAGAAUAACCUGCUGGAAAUGGGAUUCCUUGGCUAGGAAGAGCACUCAGAAUAACCUGCUGGAAAUGGGAUUCCUUGGCUAGGAAGAGCACUCAGAAUAACCUGCUGGAAAUGGGAUUCCUUACCUAGGAAGAGCACUCGGAAUAACCUGCUGGAAAUGGGAUUCCUUACCUAGGAAGAGCACUCGGAAUAACCUGCUGGAAAUGGGGUUCCUUCCCUAGGAAGAGCACUCGGAAUAACCUGCUGGAAAUGGGGUUCCUUCCCUAGGAAGAGCACUCGGAAUAACCUGCUGGAAAUGGGGUUCCUUCGCUAGGAAGAGCACUCGGAAUAACCUGCUGGAAAUGGGAUUCCUUCGCUAGGAAGAGCACUCGGAAUAACCUGCUGGAAAUGGGAUUCCUUCGCUAGGAAGAGCACUCGGAAUAACCUGCUGGAAAUGAGAUUCCUUCCCUAGGAAGAGCACUCGGAAUAACCUGCUGGAAAUGGGAUUCCUUCGCUAGGAAGAGCACUCGGAAUAACCUGCUGGAAAUGAGAUUCCUUCGCUAGGAAGAGCACUCGGAAUAACCUGCUGGAAAUGGGAUUCCUUCGCUAGGAAGAGCACUCGGAAUAACCUGCUGGAAAUGAGAUUCCUUCGCUAGGAAGAGCACUCGGAAUAACCUGCUGGAAAUGGGAUUCCUUCGCUAGGAAGAGCACUCGGAAUAACCUGCUGGAAAUGGGAUUCCUUCGCUAGGAAGAGCACUCGGAAUAACCUGCUGGAAAUGGGAUUCCUUCCCUAGGAAGAGCACUCGGAAUAACCUGCUGGAAAUGAGAUUCCUUCCCUAGGAAGAGCACUCGGAAUAACCUGCUGGAAAUGGGAUUCCUUCGCUAGGAAGAGCACUCGGAAUAACCUGCUGGAAAUGGGAUUCCUUCGCUAGGAAGAGCACUCAGAACAACCUGCCUGCUUGAGGGUGACAGCAAGUGUCUCACACUUCUCGUCUACUCCAAGUCAGAUUCCUAAAAAUAAAAUAGAGCUCCAAUGGGCAAUUUAAGCAAAAGCCUUAGAAACAUGGACACCUGAAAUGCUGGCCUACAUGAAGGGUACGAUGACAUUUUAUAUAUUAAAUAAAAAUUCCCAGUCCUGUUUUAGUAUUCAUCAGAAUAGCCUCUUGGACCCUCGAAGUUCUACACCUUUGGGAGAUAUAAAUUUCCUUAAAAUAAAGGGAUUGCUUCUUUGUGUAAAUAGCUUUCAUUUUCUCCAUCUGGAAGUGAUUUCUGCCUGCAUGUUGGAGCACAAAAUACUGCAGUUAAUUAAAGCAUUACUGGAUGUCAUUUGCUAGAAUGUAUUUCCUUACUGCUGACAGAAAACAGAACAGACUCUAGGAAAGAAGUAGCAAGUCCGUGACCCUGGCCGCUCCUGGUGGCUGCCCUUCUCCCUUCCCUGACAGUCUAAGGAAGCAACGCGUGGGAGCAGAAUGUGGCCGACUGAGCCCAGUCCUGACCUGCCCAGUUGCAGUGGAGCCUGUCUGUAAUGUUGUGUAAAGUGUUUUGCUUCUGACUUGGAACCCUACUUGCCCUGUGAAUUUCUAUCCUGUGAACCUUCCCUUCUCUGUCCUUACCGUUCCCAUCACAGCCUGCUCUUCCAGUGACGGCCAAGUGAUUUCUCUCCUGCACGCAUGAGUCCAUCCUGUUUCCUUAGUAGCUGGAUGGACGUUUUGCCAUGAAAACUCUUUGGGAAGUCUUGUGUCCUUUAGUGAUUUCUCUCCUGCACGCAUGAGUCCAUCCUGUUUCCUUAGUAGCUGGUUGGACGUUUUUGCCAUGAAAACUCUUCGGGAAGUCCUGUGUCCUUUCAACAGGGGAAAACUGGCUGCGGCCCUUCCAUUAGGCUCCAGGAUCAUUACCUCGUUUCCAUUCUUUCUUUUCAACAGCUCCCCACUUUACUAGGGAAGCCAAGGGAUCAACCUAAUGAGAAAAGAACCUUCCCUGUAGCCCACCUGGAAGGGCAUUGCCUGCCAGCUCCUUCCUUCUCACCUAUGUGAACAGGAGGGAAGAUGCCGGCGAUCCAUGGAUCUGUGGGACAUGAAGGACGUGUCCAUCAGAAAUGAAAGCAGCCUGGGAUUGGAAGCAUCCACAGAAGACUUGAUCUGCAGGUCUUGAUUUGGACCUGGCACUUUGACACCAGGCGAGUCACUGAUCCCCUGAGCAUCCAUUUUCAAUAUUGGUGAGAGGGGAUUAUAAUGAAUAUUGGCUGUGAAGGUCACACAAGACCGGGCUAUAUGCACUUGCUCUGCCAUAAGGCAGUGUGAAGUGUGUUCGUGAUCACUUGUGGGCGGGAGCCUGUGGCUGUCUUGCCUGGACUGGCUUUUUUAAACAUGGAUGAGUGGUGACAAAUCCUGCGGCCGUGUGCAGGCUACAUCCGCAGCGAGCUCCGCAUAUCUGGUCUUUGCCUUUUUAGGUCAUGACUGUAAUAUCAAGCUUACACGAGAGUUUUAAAAGACUGAGCAGUAUCCCCUUCCCCUGGCAGCUGCUGCUUCCGUAGCAUUUAGGGAUAAACCUGCAGACACUGAGAAGAGAGCUUCCUCCCUCCUGGGGCUGGUGGCGAGGCUGCCUGUUGUGGAAAAUAGGGCAUGUCUCCUGUGAAUGCGAAUUGCGAGGGUUGCCAAAGCCUCCCUUCCAAGAAACUUGCUUAGGUGUCUGGUGUCCACAGACCAGACUCUUCUCCCGACAGGGACAAAAAUUCUUGCCUGCCUUUCUUUUUCUUUUUUUUCCUUUUACUUAUUCUUGCCUUUUUUCUUCUUCUUCUUCUUUAGGUAUGAUGCCCCCCAAAAAACUAAGCAAGAUUAACUUGGGACAGGCAGUUCUAACUGGGAAGCCUGAGCUCACAGGCUGUUUGGAUUACUUUCCAAUUGUGUUUCAAAGAUGUUUAGACUUUUCCCAAGGCCAGCUGAAUCCUUAUAAUCAGCCCAAAAGUUCCUUUCUGUUUCUGUCUGUCCCCUUUGAGGGUGUUGACUCAGAGAACCUGGGGCAAUAUGAGAUGUUAAAAUAAAAAUAGCGUCCAACGUCCCGCCUCCUGGGAAUGCUGCUCACUUCAUCCGAGGGUUCUGGGAGCUUCUGCUCAGUCAUCAAAUGGAAUUUGCACAAUUGUCUUGCCUCCUGUUUUGGGUAAUUUUUCAACAAGUGAGAAAUUAAGAACAGCUUCUCAACAAACUUCCCUCUACUUCCAGGGCCAAGAAAAGUAUUUGCAGUGUGGGCUGCAGCUUUCAGGGGUCUCAGGUGAAAUGGUGGCAAGAAACCCCAGCUCCCUUCAUGUGUUUGCCUUGCGCUGAUGGAAAAGGAAGGCACUUCUCAGCUGCCAGAGACCACAUUCCACAGGGUUCUUCACAAAAUCAAGCACUGCAGUGGACCAACUGGAGCAGCCACUGGAGGGCUUUAGAAGGCAAAUGGAAUACAUAUCAAAUGCUAUAUAAAGAAAACAUCUGUUUACACAGAGUCCCCCACAGCCUCAUACCUACACCCAAUAUCAAAUGCUGUAUAAAGAAACAUCAGUUUACACACAGAGCCCCCCACAACCUCAUACCCACACCGAAUAUCAAAUGCUAUACAAAGAAACAUCAGUUUACACACAGAGUCCCCCACAGCCUCAUACCCAUGCCUGUCACAUCUUUGCACAGCCCUAAAGGAUCCAGAGCUUUGGAUCAGCAGCUGGCUAGCUCGGAGGCCAGAGGAGGGUGCUGAGGGGAGUGGAGGUCAGUUGGGGUAGCCCUGGGCCCUGGCUGCACAGUCCAGCUGCUGUGUGGCCUGCAUGUGGUAUCUUAGGUCAUGAGAGGGCCUGGGCAAUUCAGUGCUAUCUGUACAUGUUGGUGGGGUGGGAAGGAAAAGGUAACUGUGUAUUUACUGUGUCCUGGAUACAUUAUCUCAUCGGAUGAAAUUCCUGCUAAGUUAAGCUCCGUUUAGUGGACGGGACUUGGAGGCUCAAAGAGGGUAAGUGACAGGCCCAAGGAUAUGUGCCUAGUGAGGGGUGAGCCAGGAUUCGAUGUGUGACUAGUAAGGGGUCAGCCAGGAUUCAAUAUGUGACUAGUAAGGGGUCAGCCAGGAUUUCAUAUGGGACUAGUAAGGGGUCGGCCAGGAUUUGAUACGUGACUAGCAAGGGGACAAGCCAGGAUUUGAUAUGUGACUAGUGAGGGGCGAGCCAGGAUUCGAUAUGUGACUAGUAAGGGGUCAGCCAAGAUUUGAUAUGUGACUAGUGAGGGGCGAGACAGGAUUUGAUAUGUGACUAGUGAGGGGCGAGCCAGGAUUUGAUAUGUGACUGGUGAGGGGCGAGCCAGGAUUUGAUAUGUGACUGGUGAGGGGCGAGCCAGGAUUUGAUAUGUGACUGGUGAGGGGCGAGCCAGGAUUUGAUAUGUGACUGGUGAGGGGCGAGCCAGGAUUUGAUAUGUGACUGGUGAGGGGCGAGCCAGGAUUUGAUAUGUGACUGGUGAGGGGCGAGCCAGGAUUUGAUAUGUGACUGGUGAGGGGCGAGCCAGGAUUUGAUAUGUGACUGGUGAGGGGCGAGCCAGGAUUUGAUAUGUGACUGGUGAGGGGCGAGCCAGGAUUUGAUAUGUGACUGGUGAGGGGCGAGCCAGGAUUUGAUAUGUGACUGGUGAGGGGCGAGCCAGGAUUUGAUAUGUGACUGGUGAGGGGUGGAGCCAGUCAGGAUUUGAUAUGUGGUUAGUGAGGGGUUAGCCAGUCAGGAUUUGAUAUGUGGCUAGUGAGGGGCGAGCCAGGAUUUGAUAUGUGACUAGUAAGGGGGUGAGCCAGGAUUCAAUACGUGACAAGUGAGGGGUGAGCCAGGAUUCAAUACGUGACCAGUGAGGGGCGAGCCAGGAUUCGAUACGUGACCAGUGAGGGGCGAGCCAGGAUGCGAUACGUGACCAGUGAGGGGCGAGCCAGGAUUCCAUACGUGACUAGUGAGGGGUGAGCCAGGAUUCGAUAUGUGAGUAGUGAGGAGUGAGCCAGGAUUUGAUAUGUGGCUACUGAGGGGCGAGCCAGGAUUUGAUAUGUGACUAGUAAGGGGUCAGCCAGGAUUUGAUACGUGACUAGUCAGGGGGUCAGCCAGGAUUCGAUACGUGACUAGUAAGGGGUCAGCCAGGAUUUGAUAUGUGACUAGUGAGGGGUGAGCCAGGAUUUGACAUGUGACUAGUGAGGGGUGAGCCAGGAUUCAAUAUGUGACUAGUGAGGGGUGAGCCAGGAUUCGAUAUGUACCUAGUGAGGGGUCAGCCAGGAUUUGAUAUGUGGCUAGUAAGGGGUGAGCCAGCCAGGAUUUGAUAUGUGACUAGUGACGAGUGAGCCAGGAUUUGAUAUGUGACUAGUAAGGGGGUGAGGCAGGAUUUGAUAUGUGACUAGUAAGGGGGUGAGGCAGGAUUUGAUAUGUGACUGGUGAGGGGUGAGACAGGAUUUGAUAUGUGACUAGUGAGGGGUGAGCCAGGAUUUGCUAUGUGACUAGUAAGGGGGCGAGCCAGGAUUUGGCUCCAGCCUUCAUUCCAACAUCCAUGCCUUUUGUACUUCACCAGCAGUUUUCAAAUUUAUGGGACAAAAUUUUACAUUGGAUUCCCUCUAUACAAAAUAGAUAAAAGUAUUUUAUGAAUACAUUUUAUGAGUUCAAAUAUUUUUCAGAAGAAAUCAGUAAAAGCAUUGAAAACUAUUCCAGCAAAUAGGAAGCACUUUAAACCAAGGUUAUGGAUGAAAAUGUGUGUGUAUCAACCCCAGUUUACUUCUGGGUUGCACAGAAUAGAGAAAUCUUGAUUUAAUCCAGCUAAGAAUUUUCAAAUAGUAUCCAUUUUGUUUUGUUUUAAACAGCUCUUCUUGCAAUGGUAGAGGCUCUUCAAUUAAACAGAGAUGGUAACAGGC